CUUUUCCCUCCCCCUGGAGCUGUAGCGGCAGCAGCAGCAGGAAGCCGAGCCGGGUUGAGCGACUCGGAGGCGAGCGGAGGAGCUGGAAUAUGGGGAGUCAGCGAGGACGGUGGGGCCAGGAGCCCUUGGGAGGGCCUACGGAGGGAGCGGCCCCAGGCGCUUUCUAGAGCGUGAGCGGUGGGGGAGCAGGCGCAGGGUGGCACGAGCGGAGGCGGGGCCCGGGCGUGGGGCACGGCUGGGGAAGCUGCCGCCUCCGGCCCUGCCCGGCUGCCUCCGCCGCGGCCAGUGGCUAUGGAGCAGGCGGGCACCAGACCUGCGGCGACAGAGCAUCCACGGCUCCGGCGGCCCAUGCCCUGGCUGCUGCUACUGCCUCUCCUGCUGCUGUUGCUGCUGCUGCUACCUGGCCCUGCGGCCUCCCAGCUGCGAUACUCUGUGCCAGAGGAGCAGGCACCCGGCGCGCUCGUGGGCAACGUGGCUCGCGCGCUGGGGCUUGAGCUGCGGCGCUUGGGGCCGGGUUGCUUGCGCAUCAACCAUCUGGGUGCGCCCAGUCCGCGCUACCUGGAGCUGGACCUGACGAGUGGAGCGCUCUUCGUCAACGAGCGCAUUGAUCGGGAGGCGCUGUGUGAGCAGCGGCCUCGCUGCCUGCUCAGCUUGGAAGUGCUGGCGCACAACCCCGUGGCGGUGAGCGCCGUUGAGGUGGAAAUAUUGGACAUCAACGACAACUCACCGCGUUUCCCGCGGCCCAACUACCAGCUUCAGGUAAGCGAAUCGGUGGCGCCUGGAGCGCGCUUUCACAUAGAGAGUGCGCAGGACCCCGACGUGGGCGCCAACUCAGUACAGACCUACGAGCUCAGCCCCAGCGAGCACUUCGAGCUGGACCUUAAGCCCCUGCAGGAGAACAGUAAAGUGCUUGAGCUGGUGCUGCGUAAGGGCCUAGACCGGGAGCAGGCAGCCUUGCACCACCUGGUUCUCACAGCCGUGGAUGGGGGCAUCCCAGCCCGCUCGGGUACGGCACAGAUCUCUGUGCGUGUCCUGGACACUAACGACAACUCUCCUGCCUUUGACCAGUCCACUUAUCGCGUCCAGCUACGGGAGGACUCACCCCCAGGCACAUUGGUGGUGAAGCUGAAUGCCUCAGACCCGGAUGAGGGCUCCAAUGGUGAGCUCAGGUACUCCUUGAGCAGCUACACGUCGGACCGGGAGAGGCAGCUCUUCAGCAUAGAUGCCAGUACCGGGGAAGUGCGAGUAAUUGGGGGGCUGGAUUAUGAGGAAGCCUCCUCCUACCAGAUCUAUGUGCAGGCGACUGACCGGGGUCCAGUGCCCAUGGCAGGUCACUGCAAGGUGCUGGUGGACAUCGUGGACGUGAAUGACAAUGCCCCAGAGGUGGUGCUCACGGACCUGUAUAGCCCAGUGCCUGAGAAUGCUACACCCAACACCAUUGUGGCCGUUCUCAGUGUCAAUGACCAAGACUCAGGCCCCAACCGGAAAGUGAGCCUGGGUCUGGAGGCCACACUGCCUUUCCGACUGAAUGGCUUUGGAAACUCCUAUACACUGGUGGUGAGCGGCCCACUGGACCGAGAGCGGGUGGCUGUCUACAACAUCACGGUGACAGCCACAGAUGGGGGAAUACCGCAGCUCACAUCCCUGCGUACACUGAAGGUUGAGAUCUCUGACAUCAAUGACAAUCCACCAAGCUUCCUGGAGGACUCCUAUUCCAUCUACAUACAGGAGAACAAUUUGCCAGGUGUGUUGCUCUGUACUGUGCAAGCCACAGACCCAGAUGAAAAGGAGAAUGCAGAGGUGACCUACUCCCUUCUGGAGAGGGAGAUUCAAGGGCUGCCAGUCACCUCCUAUGUCUCCAUUAACAGUGCCAGUGGCAGCCUUUAUGCUGUCAACUCCUUUGACUAUGAGAAGUUUCGGGAGUUCUUUGUGACUGUGGAGGCUCAGGACAAGGGGAGCCCACCACUGAGCAGCACUGUGACUGCCAACGUAUAUGUGGUGGACAUGAAUGACCAUGCCCCUCACAUUCUGUACCCUACCUCAACCAACUCGUCAGCAGCCUUCGAGAUGGUGCCUCGAACUGCCCCUGCUGGCUACCUGGUCACCAAAGUCAUAGCUAUGGACUCAGACUCUGGGCAAAAUGCUUGGCUUUUUUACCAUCUAGCCCAGACUUCUGACCUGGACCUCUUUAAGGUAGAGCUGCACACAGGAGAAAUUAGGACUACCAGGAAGAUGGGAGAUGAGAGUGGUAGCACUUUCAACCUGACCGUGGUGGUCCGAGAUAAUGGAGAGCCAUCACUAUCAGCCUCUGUGGCCAUUACAGUAGCUGUGGUGGAUAGGGUUUCCAAAAUCCUCCCUGACACUCAGAGGCAUGUUAAGAGCCCUCGGACAUACUCUGAAAUUACCCUUUAUCUAAUAAUAGCAUUAAGCACAGUGUCUUUUAUAUUUCUUUUGACAAUCAUCAUUUUGAGCAUCAUCAAGUGCUACCGCUACACUGCGUAUGGCACUGCAUGCUGUGGAGGCUUCUGUGGAGUAAGGGAAAGGUCCCCUGCAGAACUGUACAAACAAGCCAACAACAAUAUUGAUGCCAGGAUACCGCAUGGCCUCAAAGUGCAGCCUCACUUCAUUGAAGUUCGAGGGAAUGGCUCCCUCACCAAGACCUACUGCUACAAGGCCUGUCUGACAGCAGGCUCAGGGAGUGACACUUUCAUGUUUUACAAUACAGGGGCCCAGACAGGACCAGGGCCUUCGGGAGCCCAAGCAGCAGUGACUGACAGCAGGAAUCUCACAGGCCAAAGUGGUCAGAAUGCUGGGAACCUGAUUAUUCUCAAAAAUGAGGCUGUUUCUCAAAAUGAGCCACGACAGCCCAACCCUGACUGGCGUUACUCUGCCUCCCUGAGAGCAGGCAUGCACAGCUCUGUGCACCUAGAGGAGGCUGGCAUUCUACGGGCUGGUCCAGGAGGGCCUGAUCAGCAGUGGCCAACAGUAUCCAGUGCAACACCAGAACCAGAGGCAGGAGAAGUGUCCCCUCCAGUCGGUGCGGGUGUCAACAGCAACAGCUGGACCUUUAAAUACGGACCAGGCAACCCCAAACAAUCCGGUCCCGGUGAGUUGCCCGACAAAUUCAUUAUCCCAGGAUCUCCUGCAAUCAUCUCCAUCCGGCAGGAGCCUACUAACAGCCAAAUUGACAAAAGUGACUUCAUAACCUUCGGCAAAAAGGAGGAGACCAAGAAAAAGAAGAAAAAGAAGAAGGGUAACAAGACCCAGGAGAAAAAAGAGAAAGGGAACAGCACGACUGACAACAGUGACCAGUGAGGUCCUCAAAUGGAAACAAGCCACUUAGCCAGUUUUUGUAAUAAUGGCAAAUCUCUCCCAUGUAGCAAUUCCCUGCUCCUUUUUCCUAUCUACAUGAGCCCUCUUAGAGACCUCAGAAAUCUGCAGAAAGUUCCCUGUGUCUGUCUAGAACGCAUUUAACAGGUUUUGUCGUAAAAGCUUUACUAAGUCUGGUGUUAACUCUUUCUCUCCACUCUGGCUUGUUUUCAGAACCUAAAAAGCAGACCCAAGUUUCCUUUCUCCUCCGCCGCAAAGGAGAGGCUUCCCAGCCCCGCCAGUGAGAGGUUGGACUCUCUGCCCUGUGCUCCGGGGAUCCUGUCUUGAUGACACUUGCAGGGCAGGCUGAAAAGUUUUGAGAUUGAGCAGCUUGGGAGUUUGUGGCCACUGGGUAUGUGUGGCUACCGCGGGUAUGCGAGUGCCAGAUAUUGGCUGAGACGAGCCAGCUUAGACUAAUUGGUACAAGGAAGGCAAGAAAACAAAGACAAAUAAACAGCGGAAGUUAUCAGUAUGGAGGGGAAGUGUAAACUUAAAGGGACCAGACUUUCUAAAUCUUACAACUCAAGAGGUGGCAGCCACCCUCUAGGAGACAAAACUACCCCCACUGACAAGGCUUUAGGAGACCCUAAAGUCUGUUGGCUGUGACGUCAUUAUACCUAAAAUCUGCAUCAUACCUGCAAGCCAACAGUUCAGUGUUUUAACAGAGAACCACCCUGGGAAACAGAAGCAGAUCUGAUGUGUUUCCUAUACAUGUCCUGUGCUCACUUUAUUAAAAAUUCUUUUGCACACAAUGUUUAUGAAAAGGCCAGAUCCUUUUCCAAUACUUAUGCAAAAGCAAAAGAAAACCCCGACACCUCACCUUUCGCUGUUUGUUGUUUCAUAGAUUUAUUUAAAAAAAGAGAAAGUCUAUAGCUAUAAAUCUUUAAAGAGAAAUAUGAAUACAAUUCCCCUAAACUCUCCUCAAAAGAGAAUUCAGUCUACAGCCAUUUAAAUGAUCAUUGCUGCUACAGAAGUGCUUUAAGAGAAUUGCCUGAAACAUCUGUAUUAUAUCGGCCACCUGCCAAUCACAGCUUUACUCUUUCAGGUCACUCUGGGGCUGCCUCUUGCAUGUAUUACUAAAUAAAAUGAUCUCUCUUUCUCUCUCUCUCUCUCUUUUCUAAGAAACAAUUAUGUGCACUUUGAUACACAACCUUCUCUAACCAACUAUAUAUCAAGACCCAAAAAUUGAAGAAAAAUAUUGUUUUCUCAUACAGUGAGCAGAUUUUUCAAUCUACUAAUUCUGUGACUUGUCUUGGUGUGCUAGCCUACACCUUCUCUUUGGUUUAGUUUUCCUUUUCUAUAACACUCUGAAUUGCUAAUCUUACUAACACCUAUGAUGUUACCUGAAAUCAAUCUCCCAUAUGUAUGCUGUAUGCUAUGCUAAGACUCCUGAAAUAUACUUACUCUGUGCUUGUGUAUGUGAAUGUUAAUGCAACUAUUACCUAGAGUGAACUUUAAGCUUUAUUGUUGAAUGUAAUUCCAUUAUAUUUCCUUUUGUACACCUGUGAAAAAGUGGAGUAGUGUUUUUUUAACCAUUGUUAAUCAGCUUUUGUGUAUGAAAGACACAGUAAAAUUUCUUUCUUAAAUCAAGAUACUGGUGAUUCAAGGAAUUUUAUUUAUGGUCCAGCCAAGAGCCAUCUCGUGCCAAGACUUCUGCUGGCAAGGGAAUGGAUAAAGCUGUUUUGUUCUAGUAACAAUUUUGGAAUGAAUACUGACAAUAUUCCAUGAGGGUGUGCAAGCACAAAUUUUACCAAUCUGACCUCUUUGAAGUUGCAGAAUGCUUUGAAAUUCUAAUGGUAUCUGAAAUAUCAGCUCAUAGAAAGUAACAAAAUUUGCUGUCACCUUAAAUAAGACAUUUUAAUUUUGUUAUAAUGUACAAUUUAGAAGUUUGAUUAAUUAUAUUAUCUAUUUAGGCAUUAAUAUAAAAGAGGUAGGAGUCUGUUAUUUAAAAAAAGCAUUAAAUUUAAAAAAAAACUGUCUUGUCUACUUUUAGCUUCAUUCUCCCAUAUUUUGAAGGGUGUGUAACUUCAGCUCUGCAGGAUUGCAUGGGGUAAAACUUGUUACCAACACAUGUGAACCAUUGCUACAUUGUAGGUUGUGAUCAUUUUGCCCCACUGAAGCCCAUGUAUCUGACCUUACGUGCCUUUUGAACUAGGAGAAUCGGGCUAAUUUAUUAAUGAUGAUAAUUAUAAUGUAUCUGUACAGCACUUUUUACAUUUGCGAAGUGCUUUCCAAUCCAUGUUAGUUACUAGUUAUUACAGCUGUAAGGAUAAAACACGUCAUGUGGAUUCAUUUUGAAUUGGUGCUAUUGGUAUUUCCUCUGUUAUUGCUAAUAAAUGAAAAUGGUGGUAUGAAA